UGGGCCCUCUCCCUGGCAUGAACACCUUUCACAUCACUUCUCCUCAGGAGCUAUAUUGUGGCCAGAGGCAACCAUGGAUGCUACAUGUAUUUUGUGUCAAAUGGCUGCCCAGCGUGGGAUGAGGAGGCCGCACAGGAUGCAACAGUGAUAGGAUCAAUCACUCCACCCUUCACCAGAUACUGGAGGCGUGGACAUCUACAUCAGGUAAUGGAACUCAUUGUCAUCAAGGAUGGACAAGCAAUUGUGAUUGACACAAGGUCGUAAGCUGCAGCAUAUCUUGAUGUGGAUGAAACUUCUGGAAAAAUAGAAUGCCUCUAUUUAAUUCAUUAUGCUGGUUUCCAACAAUUCAUGUGACUCCUCCAUCUUUUAUUCUUAAUGGAAUACCUGGUCUGGAAAGAGUACAUGUAUGGAUCUCCCUCCCACUCUGCACAAUGUACAUCAUCUUCCUUGUGGGGAAUCUUGGUCUUGUGUACCUCAUUUAUUAUGAGGAGUCCUUACAUCAUCCGAUGUAUUUUUUUUUUGGCCAUGCUCUCUCCCUCAUUGACCUCCUUACCUGCACCACCACUCUACCCAAUGCACUCUGCAUCUUCUGGUUCAGUCUCAAAGAAAUUAACUUCAAUGCUUGCUUGGCCCAGAUGUUCUUUGUUCAUGGGUUCACAGGUGUGGAGUCUGGGGUGCUCAUGCUCAUGGCUCUAGACCGCUAUGUAGCCAUUUGCUACCCUUUGCGUUAUGCUACCACACUCACCAACCCUAUCAUUGCCAAGGCUGAGCUUGCCACCUUCCUGAGGGGUGUAUUGCUGAUGAUUCCUUUCCCAUUCUUGGUUAAGCGUUUGCCUUUCUGCCAAAGCAAUAUUAUCUCCCAUACGUACUGCGACCACAUGUCUGUAGUAAAGCUAUCUUGUGCCAGCAUCAAGGUCAAUGUAAUCUAUGGUCUAAUGGUUGCUCUCCUGAUUGGAGUGUUUGACAUUUGUUGUAUAUCUUUGUCUUACACUUUGAUCCUCAAGGCAGCGAUCAGCCUCUCUUCAUCAGAUGCUCGGCAGAAGGCUUUCAGCACCUGCACUGCCCAUAUAUCUGCCAUCAUCAUCACCUAUGUUCCAGCAUUCUUCACUUUCUUUGCCCACCGUUUUGGGGGACACACAAUUCCCCCUUCUCUUCACAUCAUUGUGGCUAAUCUUUAUCUUCUUCUUCCCCCAACUCUAAACCCUAUUGUUUAUGGAGUAAAGACAAAACAGAUACGCAAGAGUGUCAUAAAGUUCUUCCAGGGUGAUAAGGGUGCAGGUUGAUUCAAGGCAACUUAAUUCAGAUGGAAGAAAGAUAAAUGAAAAAUAACAAAGAAUAAACUUACGUGUGAUAUUUUACAUUUAUUCAUGUGUAGUAUCAUACAUUUUCUCUCUCAGUCUAUGUUUUCUGAAACUGUUUUGGGGAAAUUUAUAGCCCAUUCUGGAUGUAUAUCUCAGUGCCUUUCCCUUAAUUUUUGUCUAUUGCCAGUUUUUAAAAAAUGAGUUUAACUCAAUUUAUUUAAAUUGACACAUAAAGUUAAAUAUGUCAUAUAUAACAUAAUGUUUUAAAUAUAUAUAAACCUUACAGAAUGGCUAAAACUAGUUCAAUUCAUAGAAGUAAAAAGUAGAAUGGUGUUUUUUUAAAAAUCACGUGUUAUUUUUCUAAAUUUUUUAAAUUGAUACAUAAUAGUUUUACACAUUUGGGAGGUGCAAAUGAUAUUUUGAUACAUGCAUAAAAUGUGUAAUAAUUCAAUCAAGGUAAUUAGAAUAUCCAUCACCUCAAACAUUUAUCUUUUCUUUUUAUUGGAAACAUUCAAAUUCUCUUUGAGCCAUGUUGAAACACGUAAUAAAUUAUUGUUAACUACAGUUAUCCACUGUACUAUUGAACACUAUGUCUUAUUCUUUUUAACUGUAUUUUAGUACCUAUUAAUUAACCUCUUUUCAUCCUCUCUUCCUCCCACCAUUCCCAGCAUCUGGUAACCACCAGUCUACUCUCUAUCUCCUUGAGAUCCACCUUUUUAGCUCCCACAUAUAAAUGAGAACAACAAUAUAUAUCCAAAAAAAGAAAAACAAUAUGUUGAAGAGAUACCAGAUACCUGCACUCCCAUGUUUGUUGCAACAUUGUUCACAAUAGCCAAGACAUGAAAUCAACCUGUGUCCAUCAACAGAGAAGUGGAUAAAGAAAAUGUGGCAUCAUAAAAAAUGAUGAAAUUCUGUAAUUUGCAGCAUCAUGGAUGAAGCUGGAAAUUAGCAUGUUAAAUGAAAUAAGCCAGCCACAGAAAGACAAAAGUUACAUUGCCCGUUUUAAUCAAGUCGUUGGUAUGAAUUCACACAACUUUUAUCUAAUAUAUUCAUCUUGGAUAUAUUCUUAAACUUUGAAAGAGUCCUUAAGUGUCUUGUCUAUGUUGAUAAUCUUUCCUAUAGAACAUUUUCCAGCCCAGUCAGUCUUUGAAGCUAAAAUUAGGUUUAUGAAUUAAUUUUGAGAAAUAUUUUUAUGUAUAUAUUAGAAUGGACAGACAAGUCUUAUUUACCUCAAGGCUUGCGUACACCAGAAGUCAGUGCAGGAGCUAGUUGGUAUAUGGUAUGGCUUUCCCAGUUAAAUGUCAACCAAUUGGUGAAAUGAUUGAUUAAAUCAUUGAUUCACUGAUUCAUUCAUUCAUGCUUCAUUUGUUAGUUAUUUCAUUUCCCAUAUUUCUGAAUAUUUUUAUCAACUCAGCUAAAUCUUAAAAUAGAACUUAUCAUUACCUCUUCCUGGUUGUCACACACACUAUAUUAUCAC